GCUUGCGCGCGUGAGCUGAGCCGGUGGGUGAGCGGCGGCCACGGCAUCCUGUGCUGUGGGGGCUACGAGGAAAGGACCUCCCACCCUCCCCCACUGAGCUGCCUUCCCAGUGAUGAAAGAAAAAAUGUAAAAGCCUGAAAACCCUUCUUCUUGAUUUUUAAUUUUUUUUUUUCCCUCUAAGACCUUAACCACUCUGGAUAGUAUCACGGGGUAUCAGUAGAGUGUGCUAAACAGAUGUGUACUCUGCAGCUUCUUUGCAGGUUUUUUGUCACAUUUUUCAGUCAAGUGUUCCAGCUUUGUGCUUGUUCAUUAGAGUCACCUGUGACUACAGAGAUUCUGAAAGUUUGAAUCAGGGCCUGGGAAUCUGUACUUUGAACAGUACUACAGGUGGUAUUUAUGCCUAGGCAAGUAUGGGAAACAACUGUGCAGAAGGAUAAAGACGUUCUUAUCUAUGACUAGACCAUCUGAAUGAUUUGGCCUUUGAAGGUGACUCAAGGUUGAGCCUGGAUGUUGGAGACUUGGUGCUAUAGACCAAGGAAGCUGCCAAGUAUUUCGCUGGUUCCUAAUCUCAUGAACAUCAGAAUCACCUGAAAAACAUUUAAAGCUACGAAUGUCUGAAUUCAGCUUCAGAGACUCUAAAUCAAUAGGAGAAACUUAAAGCUUCCUAGAUGAUUCUAAUAACCAGCCAUGUUUGAAGACCAGACCACCAAUGCGUACAAGAAGUAAAGGAUUUGGAGUCAACAUUUAAACCUUGGUUCUUUCACUUUUAAUUCUUAUGAACUUGGGCAAAAGGAUUAAAAUUCUACUUUGGUAUCUUUUGAAAGAAAACAGAAAGUGGACAUUUUAACUAUAAGUUUCUUAUCAGCCUACAAUCAGAUGAAGGAAACUGAUCUAAUUAUCAUGGACCUGCGACAGUUUCUUAUGUGCCUGUCCCUGUGCACAGCCUUUGCCUUGAGCAAACCCACAGAAAAGAAGGACCGUGUACAUCAUGAGCCUCAGCUCAGUGACAAGGUUCACAAUGAUGCUCAGAGUUUUGAUUAUGACCAUGAUGCCUUCUUGGGUGCUGAAGAAGCAAAGACCUUUGAUCAGCUGACACCAGAAGAGAGCAAGGAAAGGCUUGGAAAGAUUGUAAGUAAAAUAGAUGGCGACAAGGACGGGUUUGUCACUGUGGAUGAGCUCAAAGACUGGAUUAAAUUUGCACAAAAGCGCUGGAUUUACGAGGAUGUAGAGCGACAGUGGAAGGGGCAUGACCUCAAUGAGGACGGCCUCGUUUCCUGGGAGGAGUAUAAAAAUGCCACCUACGGCUACGUUUUAGAUGAUCCAGAUCCUGAUGAUGGAUUUAACUAUAAACAGAUGAUGGUUAGAGAUGAGCGGAGGUUUAAAAUGGCAGACAAGGAUGGAGACCUCAUUGCCACCAAGGAGGAGUUCACAGCUUUCCUGCACCCUGAGGAGUAUGACUACAUGAAAGAUAUAGUAGUACAGGAAACAAUGGAAGAUAUAGAUAAGAAUGCUGAUGGUUUCAUUGAUCUAGAAGAGUAUAUUGGUGACAUGUACAGCCAUGAUGGGAAUACUGAUGAGCCAGAAUGGGUAAAGACAGAGCGAGAGCAGUUUGUUGAGUUUCGGGAUAAGAACCGUGAUGGGAAGAUGGACAAGGAAGAGACCAAAGACUGGAUCCUUCCCUCAGACUAUGAUCAUGCAGAGGCAGAAGCCAGGCACCUGGUCUAUGAAUCAGACCAAAACAAGGAUGGCAAGCUUACCAAGGAGGAGAUCGUUGACAAGUAUGACUUAUUUGUUGGCAGCCAGGCCACAGAUUUUGGGGAGGCCUUAGUACGGCAUGAUGAGUUCUGAGCUACGGAGGAACCCUCAUUUCCUCAAAAGUAAUUUAUUUUUACAGCUUCUGGUUUCACAUGAAAUUGUUUGCGCUACUGAGACUGUUACUACAAACUUUUUAAGACAUGAAAAGGCGUAAUGAAAACCAUCCCGUCCCCAUUCCUCCUCCUCUCUGAGGGACUGGAGGGAAGCCGUGCUUCUGAGGAACAACUCUAAUUAGUACACUUGUGUUUGUAGAUUUACACUUUGUAUUAUGUAUUAACAUGGCGUGUUUAUUUUUGUAUUUUUCUCUGGUUGGGAGUAUGAUAUGAAGGAUCAAGAUCCUCAACUCACACAUGUAGACAAACAUUAGCUCUUUACUCUUUCUCAACCCCUUUUAUGAUUUUAAUAAUUCUCACUUAACUAAUUUUGUAAGCCUGAGAUCAAUAAGAAAUGUUCAGGAGAGAGGAAAGAAAAAAAAUAUAUGCUCCACAAUUUAUAUUUAGAGAGAGAACACUUAGUCUUGCCUGUCAAAAAGUCCAACAUUUCAUAGGUAGUAGGGGCCACAUAUUACAUUCAGUUGCUAUAGGUCCAGCAACUGAACCUGCCAUUACCUGGGCAAGGAAAGAUCCCUUUGCUCUAGGAAAGCUUGGCCCAAAUUGAUUUUCUUCUUUUUCCCCCUGUAGGACUGACUGUUGGCUAAUUUUGUCAAGCACAGCUGUGGUGGGAAGAGUUAGGGCCAGUGUCUUGAAAAUCAAUCAAGUAGUGAAUGUGAUCUCUUUGCAGAGCUAUAGAUAGAAACAGCUGGAAAACUAAAGGAAAAAUACAAGUGUUUUCGGGGCAUACAUUUUUUUUCUGGGUGUGCAUCUGUUGAAAUGCUCAAGACUUAAUUAUUUGCCUUUUGAAAUCACUGUAAAUGCCCCCAUCCGGUUCCUCUUCUUCCCAGGUGUGCCAAGGAAUUAAUCUUGGUUUCACUACAAUUAAAAUUCACUCCUUUCCAAUCAUGUCAUUGAAAGUGCCUUUAACGAAAGAAAUGGUCACUGAAUGGGAAUUCUCUUAAGAAACCCUGAGAUUAAAAAAAGACUAUUUGGAUAACUUAUAGGAAAGCCUAGAACCUCCCAGUAGAGUGGGGAUUUUUUUCUUCUUCCCUUUCUCUUUUGGACAAUAGUUAAAUUAGCAGUAUUAGUUAUGAGUUUGGUUGCAGUGUUCUUAUCUUGUGGGCUGAUUUCCAAAAACCACAUGCUGCUGAAUUUACCAGGGAUCCUCAUACCUCACAAUGCAAACCACUUACUACCAGGCCUUUUUCUGUGUCCACUGGAGAGCUUGAGCUCACACUCAAAGAUCAGAGGACCUACAGAGAGGGCUCUUUGGUUUGAGGACCAUGGCUUACCUUUCCUGCCUUUGACCCAUCACACCCCAUUUCCUCCUCUUUCCCUCUCCCCGCUGCCAAAAAAAAAAAAAAAGGAAACGUUUAUCAUGAAUCAACAGGGUUUCAGUCCUUAUCAAAGAGAGAUGUGGAAAGAGCUAAAGAAACCACCCUUUGUUCCCAACUCCACUUUACCCAUAUUUUAUGCAACACAAACACUGUCCUUUUGGGUCCCUUUCUUACAGAUGGACCUCUUGAGAAGAAUUAUCGUAUUCCACGUUUUUAGCCCUCAGGUUACCAAGAUAAAUAUAUGUAUAUAUAACCUUUAUUAUUGCUAUAUCUUUGUGGAUAAUACAUUCAGGUGGUGCUGGGUGAUUUAUUAUAAUCUGAACCUAGGUAUAUCCUUUGGUCUUCCACAGUCAUGUUGAGGUGGGCUCCCUGGUAUGGUAAAAAGCCAGGUAUAAUGUAACUUCACCCCAGCCUUUGUACUAAGCUCUUGAUAGUGGAUAUACUCUUUUAAGUUUAGCCCCAAUAUAGGGUAAUGGAAAUUUCCUGCCCUCUGGGUUCCCCAUUUUUACUAUUAAGAAGACCAGUGAUAAUUUAAUAAUGCCACCAACUCUGGCUUAGUUAAGUGAGAGUGUGAACUGUGUGGCAAGAGAGCCUCACACCUCACUAGGUGCAGAGAGCCCAGGCCUUAUGUUAAAAUCAUGCACUUGAAAAGCAAACCUUAAUCUGCAAAGACAGCAGCAAGCAUUAUACGGUCAUCUUGAAUGAUCCCUUUGAAAUUUUUUUUUUGUUUGUUUGUUUAAAUCAAGCCUGAGGCUGGUGAACAGUAGCUACACACCCAUAUUGUGUGUUCUGUGAAUGCUAGCUCUCUUGAAUUUGGAUAUUGGUUAUUUUUUAUAGAGUGUAAACCAAGUUUUAUAUUCUGCAAUGCGAACAGGUACCUAUCUGUUUCUAAAUAAAACUGUUUACAUUCAUUAUGGGGUAUGUAUGACCUUCAUUUUCCAAGAAAUAGAACUCUAGCUUAGAAUUAUGGAUGCUCUAAAAUGUCAGAAUGGGAACUCUCCUCGAAGUUCUCCCAAACUCAGAGACAGCACUGCCUUCUCCUAAAUGAUUAUUCUUUUCUCCCUGUUUUCUGGUAUUUUCUAGCAUCCUUCUCACCACAGCCAUAACCCUUUUUUACUUCCAUUAGGCCGUAUAACUGGAGAGACCUGCUGCUCGUUAUAUAAUUAUCUGAUACCAAACACAAGCGAUUCUGAAUGUACACACACGUUUAUCUAUAGAGCAUAAGGUAAAACAAUUUUGUUUAACAUUUUGGUAUUGUUUACAAAUGUUAUUAAAACAUGCAAAUUCAUUUUGAGAACCUCGAGAGAAUUAAACUAUUAACUUUAGUAAACACACAGUUUAAGACAAAUAUAAAGGUUUAGCCAAAUGCAACGGGGAGGAAGCACCUGGAAUAAUUUGUGCUUGCUCAGGGGCUUGUGGACAUGGCUGUUCCUGCCAAAGCUGUAGCAGUUAUCCAAAAGUUCUUUCAAACUCAUAUUUGGGGCCACUGAGUUUUUUUUGUUUUUUUUUUUGUUUUGUUUUGUUUUUUCUUUAUGUCUCUCCCAUUUCUAAAGUGUUUUCUUAAGUUUGUUCUAAUUCAGCAUAUAUCAUCUCAGAAUGGAUCCCCAGCAGGAAAAAAAAAAAAAGUUACUAAAAAGGAAAGUAUCCAUACACUGAAAACUUAAAGCAUAUUCCUUUUUGGUUGCCUUGUAUGUAGAAAUCAGUUCUCCAAGUGCUGUGAAUGGUGCCACUUAGGAGUAGAAACUGAUGAUUGUUGAAAUGGCCUUUGGGUGGUCUGAAAUAGACCAGUGGAAACAGUAGCUUUGUAGGCAAGAAGGCAAUAGUAAGAAAAUGAAAAAUUGACUCCCCAAACUGCCAUCACUCCUUUUACCAUCUUUUUUGUGUUUUUAGUAGUUUGGUUUCUGACGGAGACAAUAGAAACUUACUUAAAAGUAAAAUUUAAUUCUAGCUGUUGCAAACAGGCCAAUAUUGGGUCCUCAGUUGGGGCCAACUUGGGUAGACGAGACAGUAGAAACUUCUGUUUUCUGGGAGCUGCAUGUGUCGGAUUCAUCUGUCAUGGCCUUCCCACACACCAUCUUCAUGAUGCAAGCUUGGAACUGGAGAGAAAGGUACAAUUGGAGAUAACCUUGGCAGAUGAGGAAGUAUGGGAAAAAAGACCUUAUUCUCUGUAUCACCAAAGCCUUGCACAAUGCUUUGUACCCAGAAUGCCCUUAGGUGGUUUUGAAUCUAUCUUCCCCAUCCUGAAAACUAUCUAGAUUCCAGUCUAGAACUACUCCUGGGUCUACGGUAAUCCUAAACUGGUCAAGUCUGAGACCUCACUGUUGGUAAAUUCACAAACCAUCCUGCUUCAUAAAAGCACUGUCAGCAGAGGCCCCUCCAUUACUAGCAGGUGCUCCCAGCUGGAAAGGACUGCCAAUUCUCUUCUAUCCAGGGAGGUUUCAAAUUAGUUUUGAGUCUACCUCUGGGAUUGAGGAAACAAUACCAUCUGAAAGUAGGGUUUUUGCCACUUAGGGUUUGGUGUUUAUUAGCUCGGAUUUCAGAUGGGAUAGGAAAUCCCCCAGUACCUUCAGAUGAUAAGAUAUUUUAGAGAUUUUUGCAUGUGGUAUGAUUUCUGUGCUUCACACAUGCUCGUGCAGGCUAAAAGUUGGAAGGGAAAUGAUUAAGAAAUUAUUAAAUGCAAGGACUGAAAAUUGAGAGGAAUCUGAGUUUUUAUUUUUAUUUUUUUAAUUUUAUUUAAGUUCCAGGAUACAUGUGCAGGAUGUGCAGGUUUGUUACAUAGGUAAACGUGUGCCAUGGUGGUUUGCUGCACGAGUUUUUCAAUAAAAUGCUUUCAUUCA